GGGAGGGUCAUGACGCAGCGAGUUUCAGUCGUGACUUUUCUGGGGGCAUCGCGGCGUCCCCUUUUUUUGCCUUUAAAGUAAAACGUCGCCCCGACGCACCCCCCGCGUAUUUCGGGGGGCGGAGGCGGCGGGCCACGGCGCGAAGAGGGGCGGUGCUGACGCCGGCCGGUCACGUGGGCGUGUUGUGGGGGGGAGGGGCGCCGCCGCGCGGUCGGUUCCGGGCGGUUGGGAGCGCGCGAGCUAGCGAGCGAGAGGCAGCCGCGCCCGCCGCCGCCCCUGCUCUGUAUGCCGCUCUCUCCCGGCGCGGCCGCCGCCGAUCACAGCAGCAGGAGCCACCGCCGCCGCGGUUGAUGUGGUUGGGCCGGGGCUGAGGAGGCCGCCAAGAUGCCGCAGUCCAAGUCCCGGAAGAUCGCGAUCCUGGGCUACCGGUCUGUGGGUUCCUCAAGCCAGGACCUACGCACCUGUUGUGAGUGGUGUUAUAGUUCUGCAGGGCGCACAGGUGCAUCCCCAUGGGCACAUUUAAUUUAGGGAAAUCCUCAUUGACGAUUCAAUUUGUUGAAGGCCAAUUUGUGGACUCCUACGAUCCAACCAUAGAAAACACUUUUACAAAGUUGAUCACAGUAAAUGGACAAGAAUAUCAUCUUCAACUUGUAGACACAGCCGGGCAAGAUGAAUAUUCUAUCUUUCCUCAGACAUACUCCAUAGAUAUUAAUGGCUAUAUUCUUGUGUAUUCUGUUACAUCAAUCAAAAGUUUUGAAGUGAUUAAAGUUAUCCAUGGCAAAUUGUUGGAUAUGGUGGGGAAAGUACAAAUACCUAUUAUGUUGGUUGGGAAUAAGAAAGACCUGCAUAUGGAAAGGGUGAUCAGUUAUGAAGAAGGGAAAGCUUUGGCAGAAUCUUGGAAUGCAGCUUUUUUGGAAUCUUCUGCUAAAGAAAAUCAGACUGCUGUGGAUGUUUUUCGAAGGAUAAUUUUGGAGGCAGAAAAAAUGGACGGGGCAGCUUCACAAGGCAAGUCUUCAUGCUCGGUGAUGUGAUUCUGCUGCAAAGCCUGAGGACACUGGGAAUAUAUUCUACCUGAAGAAGCAAACUGCCCGUUCUCCUUGAAGAUAAACUAUGCUUCUUUUUUCUUCUGUUAACCUGAAAGAUAUCAUUUGGGUCAGAGCUCCCCUCCCUUCAGAUUAUGUUAACUCUGAGUCUGUCCAAAUGAGUUCACUUCCAUUUUCAAAUUUUAAGCAAUCAUAUUUUCAAUUUAUAUAUUGUAUUUCUUAAUAUUAUGACCAAGAAUUUUAUCGGCAUUAAUUUUUCAGUGUAGUUUGUUGUUUAAAAUAAUGUAAUCAUCAAAAUGAUGCAUAUUGUUACACUACUAUUAACUAGGCUUCAGUAUAUCAGUGUUUAUUUCAUUGUGUUAAAUGUAUACUUGUAAAUAAAAUAGCUGCAAACCUCAGUCCUUUGUGCUACUUGAUGUGGCUUUCAAAGAAGAGAAGCCUUGUCCUGAGUUUCUCACUUGGCUUCAGGAAGGCCCCAGGUUGGAUUCCAGAAACCAGUGAAGAUGUGGCCACAGGAGGAGGUGUGCUGAGGUGGCUGCUGACCGUGGACUCCCUGCGCAGUGGCCUGCAGAUGUUGGGGCUGGGUUACAGCUGAUUGAAGCUGAGUGGCCCUGGGGGGUCUGUGAGGGGAGUUCCUCCCCAGUGAUGAAAUUCUCUCCUUCCACCCUCAAAUCCCUAGACCUUGACUGAAAUGCUCCGUGGUCGGGAGCCUGGUCAAGGAGGAGGAGCUGCUGAGAGGCAUUGUUCGCCCUUGCUCAUAGCUUAGCUCGAUGUCCGUGUCAGACAGGAGAUGAUUGAGAACAGCCUUGCCUGUCACUGUCCUAGAACACCCUGGAGUUUAGUGUUCUGUGUCAGAGUCUUGGGAGCCUCCUUCAGACCCAGAUGACGGGCCUCCCUCUGUCCAAGGAGCAGCUGUAAAGGAGAAGAGGGAUUUCAUUUGUUUGGUGGCUGUUACCUUGUCUGUAAGUCAAACUUGGAGUUGAGCAGUGCUUUUUAAACGAUUCCCUUUUGCAGCUAAAAUUUCACAGGGCUAUUUCUAAUACGUAAGCAAAUGUUACCAUUGACUUUAUUAAUAAAAUAUAGUUUUGCUUUGCA